GGCUUGAAUCCCGGCGCCUCAGAGGACUAUGAGGCGGGCGCCAACUGCUUGGGCCGCAGGGCGGGAGGCAGCGCGGGAGUGGGGCGUUGAGGGGCCGGCCUAGCUUGGGGCUCUGGCCUUGCGUCUUCCGACCGAAUCACCGCUCCUGAGCCCGGUGCGGGGCUGCCGCUAUCGCCUGGCCGUGGGUGCCGGAGCGGCCGGGUUGCGACUCAGCGUUCUUGGGUGGGCGCGGGCGGCGUCUCCGCGGCGGGCAUCCCCCGAGGCCGCCCUCGGGCCAUGAUCGACUCCGUGAAGCUGCGCCGCGACAGCGCGGCGGACUUCUUCUCCCACUACGAGUACCUGUGCGCGCUGCAGAACUCGGUGCCGCUGCCCGCCGUGCGCGCCUGUCUCCGGGAGGGCGUGCUGGAUUUCAACGCCGACCGCCUCCGCGGGGUGGACUGGGCGCCUCUGCUGAGCACCCUCAAGAUCAAUAAAGACCUGCCCUUGGUCUCCAUCAAGAGCUUCUUCCAGCCCUGGCUGGGGGACACAGGUUCUGACAUGAAUAAAUUUUGCAGAAGUCGUGUUCCUGCGAUAAGAUACAAAGAUGUGACCUUCCAGUUGUGUAAAGCUCUUAAAGGCUGUUUAAGUAUAUCAAGUGUGCUAAAGAACCUGGAGCUAAAUGGACUAAUUCUGAGAGAGAGGGAUUUAACUAUUCUAGCAAAGGGAUUGAAUAAAUCGGCUUCUUUGGUGCACCUGUCUCUUGCAAAUUGUCCAAUUGGAGAUGGAGGUUUAGAAAUUAUUUGUCAAGGUAUAAAGAGCUCUAUCACUCUUAAGACAGUCAACUUCACAGGAUGUAAUCUGACAUGGCAGGGAGCAGAUCACAUGGCCAAGAUCUUAAAGUAUCAGACCAUGAGAAGGCAUGAAGAAACCUGGGCUGAGAGUCUUCGCUAUAGGAGACCUGAUCUUGACUGUAUGGCUGGCUUAAGACGUAUCACACUGAAUUGCAACACACUUAUUGGUGACCUAGGUGCAUGUGCUUUUGCAGACUCUCUCAGUGAGGAUUUAUGGCUGAGAGCUCUUGACCUGCAACAGUGCGGCCUCACCAAUGAAGGAGCAAAGGCUUUGCUAGAGGCCCUUGAAACCAAUACAACUCUGGUCGUUCUGGAUAUAAGAAAAAAUCCACUCAUUGAUCAUUCUAUGAUGAAAGCAGUUAUCAAAAAAGUCCUCCAGAAUGGAAGGAGUGCCAAAUCAGAGUACCAGUGGAUAACUUCUCCAUCAGUGAAGGAACCAUCCAAAACUGCUAAACAGAAAAGGAGAACUAUAAUUCUAGGAAGUGGUCACAAAGGAAAAGCUACUAUUAGAAUUGUAGGAUUGGCUACAAAGAAACCUGUAAGUAGUGGCAGAAAACACUCCCUUGGUAAAGAAUAUUAUGCGCCCGCACCUCUUCCACCUGGUGUGUCUGGUUUCUUGCCGUGGCGUACUGCAGAACGUGCAAAAAGACACAGGGGUUUCCCAUUAAUCAAAACACGUGAUAUAUGUAAUCAGUUGCAGCAACCAGGUUUUCCUGUGACUGUGACAGUAGAGAGUCCUUCAUCCUCUGAAGUUGAAGAGGUUGAUGAUUCUUCAGAGAGUGUUCAUGAAGUGCCUGAGAAAACUAGUAUAGAACAAGAAGCAUUACAGGAAAAACUGGAGGAGUGCCUAAAGCAGUUAAAGGAAGAAAGAGUGAUAAGGCUUAAGGUUGAUAAACGAGUCAGUGAGCUGGAACAUGAAAAUGCCCAGUUAAGAAAUAUAAAUUUCUCUUUGUCUGAAGCCCUUCAUGCACAGUCAUUGACAAAUAUGAUCCUGGAUGAUGAAGGUGUUUUGGGCAGCAUUGAGAAUUCUUUUCAGAAGUUUCAUGCUUUCUUGGAUCUCCUUAAAGAUGCUGGGCUUGGGCAGCUUGCCACAAUGGCUGGGAUAGAUCAGUCAGAUUUUCAAUUACUAGGUCAUCCCCAGAUGACUUCUACUGUUAGUAAUCCACCUAAAGAAGAAAAGAAGGCGCUUGAAGAUGAAAAACCAGAACCGAAGCAGAAUGCCCUAGGGCAAAUGCAAAAUAUCCAGGUUUCUAUUUGUAUGCAGUCAGCUUACAAUGAAGGAACACUAAUGAAGUUUCAGAAAAUUACAGGUGAUGCUAGAAUUCCUUUGCCUCUCGACUCCUUUCCUGUCCCAGUUUCUACUCCAGAGGGCUUAGGAACUUCCAGCAACAACCUAGGAGUCCCAGCUACUGAGCAGCGGCAGGAGUCUUUUGAAGGAUUCAUUGCUAGAAUGUGUUCUCCUUCACCAGAUGCGACUUCUGGAACUGGAAGUCAAAGAAAAGAAGAGGAGUUGUCCAGAAAUAGCAGAUCUUCUUCAGAGAAAAAGACCAAAACAGAAUCCCAUUGAAAUGACUGGAGAAAUAUUAAAAUAAAAAUAAUAGCAGAGUUGGAAAACCAGAAAUUUGAACAGUGAAAUUUCUGGAAGAUAAGAAGCAGAUGAUUUAAGUACCAGUUAAUUAAAGGAUGGAACAGCUAAGCCAUUCCACUCAUCUUUGGAGCAUCUGAUUCUGGAGUUUGCCACCAGGCUAAGAAAGCAGCUAUCUGAAGUGGGAGCUCUGACCCAAGAAAUGCUGGGAUCGGAGAAUAAGGGAAUUAUCCAAAAUGGCUCCGAAGAGGAACUGAAGUUAAGCUGCCCACAUGAUCUCUCUAACUAUGAUGACCUGCCACUUCCGUUUAUAAUCACCAUAUAAGUGCCUGUAAUCAUUUGUGUUCAUUAAAAGUGAACCAGAAUUCCCAUUUGGAUGAAAAAAUAACACUUCCAACUUUAAUCUUAGGCCCUCAUUUAUAAAUAUGGACAACCAAGAAUCAUCAAAUUUGAAGAAAACCAGUAACAUAAAAGGAGGCAUGAAAUUAAAAUUAACCUGUUCAAGAAGAUAGUUACUAGGAGAAACAUGAAAUUUUUAAAUUAAUGAAUCAAAAUCUUCAGCAAUUCAUAAAGAUACUGUGUUCAUAAAGAAUAGGAUGCCAUGAAAAAAAUAUUUAGAGUUUCUGGAAAUUAAAAAUUUGAUUAUGAAACUGAAACACUCAGAAGAUGGACUACACAGCAGAAUGGAUUCAUUUGAAGCUUAAAUUCAUGAAAUGGAAGGUAUUAAUUGGUCUUAGACGUUUCAUCAGCAACUUAAUUACUUAGAAAAAAUCUUUCUCAGAGUAACUAAGCAAAAUGAACAAUGAACCCAUUAACGUGUGGUUUUGUUUUUUGGGUUUUUUUUUUUUGAGUCAAGGUCUCACUCAUGUCACCCAGGCUGGGGUGUAGUGAUGGGAUCACAGCUUAUUGUAACCAUGAACCAUUGGGCUUAAAUUAUCUUCCCACCUCAGCCUCCCAAGUAGCUGCAAUGUACCACCAUGCCGAAGUUUUAAAAAAUUAUUGUAGAGUUGGGUUCUUUCUUUCUUUUCUUUUUUUCUUUUUUUCUUUUUUUUUUGAGACGGAGUCUCGCUCUAUUGCCCAGGCUGGAGUGCAGUGGUACAAUCUCAGCUCACUGCAACCUCCUCGAUCUCAGCUCACUGCAACCGUGAAGUGAUCUUCCUGCCUCAGCCCCCCUAGUAACUGGGAUUACAGGCACACACCACCAUGCCUGGCUAAUUUUUGUAUUUUUAGUAAAGACGGGGUUUCACCAUGUUGGCCAGGCUGGUCUCGAACUCCUAACCUCAGGUGAUUCACCCACCUCGGCCUCCCAAAGUGCUGGGAUUACAGGCAUGAGCCACUGCAUCCGGCCAAGAUGGGUUCUUUCUUAGGCUGGUCUUGAACUCCUGGCCUCAAAUGAUCCUCCCACCUUGGCCUCCCAAAGUGCUGAGACUACAGACCUGAGCCACUGUGCCCAGCCCCAUGAAAGAUGUUUAGAUCAAAUAAACUGAUAAAGAUAUUGAUAAAGAUAUGAGACAAACUACUUCAGCUUUGUGACCUGCAAAUCCCCUUUUAUAAUCACCAGAGGUGCCUGUAGUCAGAAAAAGUCUAAAUAAAUACUAAUGACAUAUGAAAACAAAGUCCAACCAAAGUUCUAGGUUUGAACAUGAAUGGAGGCAUGGCAGGACACAGAAAGUGAAAGCUUGUCCUAGAUAUUGUCUUAUUCAUGGGAAGGAUACAGGUAGUGUUUGAUUCUAGGUAUUGAUUGAAAAAAUAUAUUAAAAUAUAUAUAAAGUUAAGGGUAUGUUAGUAAGGAUAGGUUAGGUGAUGUUGCAUUAACAGCUCCCAAAUUUUAAUUACUUUCAACAACAUAGGUUUAUUUGUGCCCAUGCAGUUUGCCUUUGGCAGAUUGGCUAGAGGCCCCUAUUCAACAUCAACCUCAAUCUGGAAGCGAGGCUGGUGGAACGUCACUAUUUGGAACAUUGCUGGUUGCAGUGUCCAAGGAAAGACAGUAUGAUGCAGCAUAUAUUGUGACUUAAAGCUUCUGUCUAGAUGUGACAUAUGUCACUUCUGUUCACAUUUCUUUGGCCAAAGAAAGUCACAUGGUUAUGCCUGAGUUCAGCAGACCAGGGAAGUGCAGAAUUGCCAUUUGCCAUGAGAAGAGAGGGAAGCAAAUGUAUGUCAACAACUUUAAUAGCUACAAAACUACCUGGAAAGAGGGAAUGGAAUUUUUAGGUCCAACAAGACGGGAAAGAAAAAGAAACAAGCUACAUAGAAAUAAAAAAUCCACAAUAUAGCAAGAUCAAGUUUUUUACUCAUAAUAAACAUGAACAGGUUAAAUUCUGGAAUCCUUAGGCUUGAGUAAAAACAUGAAAUCCCACUGUGUGCUAUUUGCAAAAUCUAAAACGCUGUCAUAGAUUAUAAAGAGAUGAACAAAAAUAUACCAGGCAGAUGCUAAAGAGUAAAUGUGGCUGUGUUAGCUGCAGACUAAAUAGAACCCAAGGUGAAAAUUGGUAAAGGGGACAAAAGCUUCUUUUGGCUGAUAAGUACAGUGUUGCAGAAGAUUUUUUAAAAAAAUAUAUCUGCAAUUUAAAAACUUGAUGUUAGGCCGGGCGCAGCGGCUCACGCCUGUAAUCCUAGCACUUUGGGAGGCCGAGGUGGGUGGAUCACCUGAGGUCAGAAGUUCAAGACCAGCCUGGCCAACAUGGCAAAACUCCGUCUCUACUAAAAAUACAAAAAAAAAAAAAAAAAAUUAGCUGGGUGUCAUGGCGCAUGCCUGUAAUCCCAGCUACUCGGGAGGCUGAGGCAGGAGAAUCGCUUGAACCUGGGAGGCGGAGUUUGCAGUGAGCUGAGAUGGCACCGCUGCACUCCAGCCUGGGCCAUAGAGGAGACUCCGUCUCAAACAAACAAAAACCUUCAUCUUAAAAUUAUAGGGUAAGAAUUUAGAAAUACAAGGAAAAAUGGCCAGCCAGUUAUAACAAGAAGCUUUAAGACAUCUCUUUUCAGAAUCAGUGGAUCGACUGCUGCACACACACUAGAAUGGCUAACAUUUUGAAAUGCUGAUAAAUAUGCAGAGCAACUGGAGUUCCUCACAGCUGGUAGGAAUGCAAAAUGACUCAGUCACUCAAAACAGUUUGGCAGAUUCUUUAAAUGCUAACAUACACAUACCAUAUGACCAAGCAGUCCCACUCCUGGGUAUUUAGAGAGAUGAAAACUUAGUUCACACAAAACCUGUGCGUGGAUAUUUAUAGCAGCUCCAUUCAUAGUGACCAAGAUGUCUUCCAACAGGUGAAUGGAUAGCGAUGUAUCCAUAUGGUGGCAAACAUGCCACAAUUCGGAUGAAUCUCAACAUCAUAUGCUGAGUGAAAAAGCCAGUCUCGGAAGGCUACAUUCUGUAUGAUUCCAUUUAUAUGGCAUUCUUGAAAAGACAAAACUAUAGUGACAGAACAGAUUGGAGAUUGCCAGGUGUUGGGGUUGGGAGGAGUUGAUUACAAAGAGGCUGUACAAGGGAGUUUGUUUGUUUGUUUGUUUUGGUGAUGAACAGUUCUGUAUCCUGAUUGCGGUGGUGGUAACGUGAGUCUAUACAUAUGUUAAAAUUUAUAGAACUGCAUACUCUCAAAAAAAUUAGUUUUACUCUAUAAUAAUAUUAGAGCUUAAAAAAUUCAUCCCUCUUGCCCAUCAGUAGAUCAGGAUAUGAAGGAUACCAUUGAACAUAAAUAUUUUGUAUCCAUGAUGAAUACAAAGUAUAUUCUCCUGGAAAACCAAUAGAACAUUCAUAUAAAUGAUUCCUAUGAAGGUAAAAAACUUACAAAAUUCAAAGAUCAUACAGAUCAUGUGCUCUGUAUAAUGUAAUAAUAGUAACAAAAGGCCUGUCCACUUGGAAAUUUUUAAAUGAUCUUCUAAAUAACUCAUUUAAAGGAGAAAUCAAAAUAAAUUGCAAAUUAUUUAGAAUUAAUAAAAACUUCUCUAAAGCUGAGGAAUUCUACCAAAGAGGUGUUAGAGGAAAUUGUAUAGAUUUUGAUUUACUUUCCAGGAAGAAAGAAGACAAAAGAGAUGAAUUAAACAUUUAAAGCUAAGAAAGAGAUAAACCAAAAGAAAGGUGAGGAAUUGGUAAAAGCAGAAAUGAAUAAAAUAGCAAAUUUUGAUCAGUGAAACACAGGUUUUUAAAAAUGAAAGAUAAACCUUUGUAAAAUAUGAUAAAGAAAAAAAAGCAAGAAGUAAUUAACAAAAAUUGCCAGCAUUAGGAAUAAUUUUAGAAGGAUACCUACAACUAGAAGAGAUAUUUUUAAUUAUGAGCACUUUUAUAAUUUACUAUAAAUAAUUGUGUAGUGUUAAACCAAUAAAUUUGAAAGACUAGAUGAAAUGUGACUGUUUAAAAAUAUGGAUUGUAAAAAUUGAUAAAAAAUAGAAAAUGUAAAUAAACGAAACAUCUUAGGAGAAAUUGAAAAAAUAGGACAAGAACUUAUUUUUAAAAAGAGGCCAGGUGCGGUGGCCCAUGCCUGUAAUACCAGUACUUUGGGAGGCCGAGGUGGGCGGAUCACCUGAGAUGAGGAGUUCAAGACCAGCCUGGCCAACAUGGUGAAACCCCGUCUCUACUAAAAAUACAAAAAUUAGCCGGGCUUGGUGGCGGGCACUUGUAAUCCCAACUACUCAGGAGUCUGAGGCAUGAGUGUCGCUUGAACCUGGGAGGCAGAGGUUGCAGUGAGCUGAGGUCACACCGUUGCACUCUAGCCUGGGAGACAAGAGGGAAACUCUGUCUCCAAAAAAAAAAAAAAAAAAAUACAGUUAGAAAAACUUUAAAGGGGCCAGGUGUGGUGGCUCAUGUCUGUAAUCCCAGCACUUUGGGACACCAAAGUGGGAACAUUGCUGAGACCAGCAGUUUGAGACCAGCCUGGGCAAGACCUCAUCUCUACAAAAAUUAAAAAACAAAACAAAACAAAAAAACCCAAAACUUAGCCAGGCAUGGUGGUGCGUGCAUGUAGUCCCAGCCACUCAGGAGGCUGAAGUGGGAGGAUCGCUUGAGGCCGGGAUUCGAGGCUGCAGUGAGCUGUGAUCAUGCCACCACUGCUCUCUAGCCUGGGCAAGAGUGAGACUCCGACUCAAGAAGAGAAAAAGAAAAACCUUCCAGGGGCACAUUUAUUUGUAAACCAUUCCAGAGGAUAGAAAAGAGAUGUAAGGCUCCCUAAUUCAUUCCAUACGGUUAGCGUAAUCCUUAUAGCAAACUGCACAAAUAAAACACAAGGAAAACUAAACCAAAUUCAAUUAAUGUAGGUGCAAAAAAUCCAAAAUAAAACUAGCAGUUUGAAUUCAGCAUUGUAGCAAAAGAUAUAUCAUUUUCAAGGAAGAUUUGUACCAAAACAUGCAAGAUUGAGUGAAGAGUAACUCACUGUAGCUCACUAAAUUAACAGAUUAAAGAAGUAUAGUCAUCUUCACAAGCUGAAAGAGUAUGUGAUAAAUUCAACAUCCUCUGGUAUUCUUAACAAUCUCGAAAUAGAAGGAAACUUCCUUAGCUUAGCUUCUUGGCUUCAUUAAAUAUACCUAACAGAAAUCCACAGGAAACAAACUUGGUGAAAAGUUUUUGCUAAGAUAAAAACGGUACUAAAAAGUACACAUUUUGGGAAAUGAGACAAGGCUCUCGUUAUUUGUAAAUAUGGGGUCUUUUUUUUUUUGGACAAAAAACCCCCUGUGAUGAUCUACUGGCAUGCUAUUACAGCUAAUAAAGCUGAAUAAGGAGGCUGUGCACAACACCAACACACCGGUAUGAAAAGUGUGUACACCAGCAAUAACCAAUUAGAAAAUGUAUGAGGAAAUAGACUCUCAUCCACAAUAGCUGCGAGAAGUAAAUAUUAUCUAGAAAUAAGAUUAACAAGAGAAAUGUAAGGCCUAUAUAAAUAAAAGGAUAAAUCUAUGCUAGAGGGUAUAAAAGAAACACAAAAAUAGAGGUAUGCCAUGUAUAAGACCCAACAUAAUAAAUAGUUCUACCAAAUUAAUUUAUAAAUUCAAAGCAAUUUCAUAUAACCACAGUAAAGCUUUUUAAAUGGAUGUAAUAACCUGAUUAUAACAUUAAUCUGAAAGUCAUCAGGCAUAAAGCAAUUUUGAUUACAUCUCAAAACAAUCCAUGGAGUUAGGGUAAAUGUGCUGUUCACACAGGAAUAAUCACAGGUAUAGAACCGAGAACCUAGGAACAGAGCAAUGUAUAUAUAUAUGUAUUUAAAAAAUGGCAUCACAAGUCAGUAGAGAAGGGUUUGAACUAUUCAGUAAAUGAUGUUGAGGUUAUUUACUACUUUUUCUUAUUUCAUAUCAUGGAUGAAAAAAAUCAAGAUGAAUUAAACAUGGAAAUUAAAAAUAACUAGAAGAAAAUACUGGAAAAAAAUUGUAAUAAAUGUGUAAGAAAGGCAUUCCCAACCAAGACACAAAACCCAGUAGCCAUGAAAAAAAAGAUAGAUUUGACUACAUUUUUAAAAAGUAAAACCUUUCACUUUUUACAAAACUUUGAUAAAAUUAGAUUUCAUAAAUAAAGGAGUGGGAAAAUACAUGUAAUAGAACAGAAGAUUUAAGAUAAUAUAAAGAGCACCUACAAACAACAAAAAUUGGACAAAGGCUAUAAAAAUAUUUUAUAAAUAAGAAAUACAGACUAUAAACAUAAACUUUCAACCUCGUAAGCAAUCAGGAAAAUUAAAGUUAAAAUGAGAUACUAUUUUUCAAUACAUUGAAAUGGCAGAUUAUUAAAGAUUGGUGAUAGUGCUGGAGAUAAUGUGAGGAAAGGAGUAUUCUCAGUCAUUGUAGAAAUUGAUACAGCUUUUGGAUGGACAGUUUGACAGUGUGUAUCAACAUGUGAAAUGUCUCCAGCCUUUGAUCUAAUGACUAAUUUUAGGCAUCCAGCCUGAAGAAAUAUUCACACAAGUGCCCAAAGAGUCAGAUACAAGACUGUGUGAAGUGUUUUUUGAGAUAAUAAAAAACUAGAAACAGCAUAAAUGUACAGAAAUGCAGAAAUUGUUGAAUUAGUACAUACCAAUUUCUGACAUAUAACACUCUGCAGCAGAUAAAGACAAUAGCUCUCUAGUGUGGACAUGAAAAUAUUUCUAAGACAUUGACAGGACGAAGAAGUUGCACAGUAACCACGCACUCCUGUUUACAUUUGUAUAGUUAAAACUUGUUUACCUAUACGUAGCAUAUAUGCGUGUGUGCACCCUAGAAAAGAGUCUGUGAUAACACAUAUCAAGCUAUUGACAGCGGUUUUGUCUGCUGAAGGAGGAAAAAAGGGGGGCUUCUCACAUUUUACUCCAUUUAAUUCUAGGUUGUUUGGUUUAAAAAAAAAGUUUUUAUGUACAACAGACAAUUUUUAAAAUUCCUUUUCAUCAUAGAAAAUGAAAAUGUGUACUCUGUUAUCCUUUACGCUCUGUCCAUUUUUUUCUUCAAAAAUGUGUCUGACCUAUUAUCAAUGUGAAUGAAAAUGAGCUUUGCUACAUAACCUCUUUUCAGAGCUUUGUAUUCCUGAAGUGUUGGAGUCGCCUACAUGGCAUAGUCAAAUGUUUUUAACUUAACCACAACCCACAGUAAAAAUGAAGCUUUCUGCAAAGUUAAAAGUAGUAGUCCUGGCCCCACCUUCCUUGUGUGCACGUAUAAUUAAUGGAAAAUUGCAUCAAACAACUCUGAUUGUACUUCUAGUGACUAAUUCAUGUUCUGUUCUAUUCCUUGCCUUUAAAGAAAAUUAUGUUGGCAACUCACGAAGUAUGUUUCACAAUCCACUAAUGGGUAAUGUCCUACUGUUUGGAAACACUGGCUAGAGUGUUUCAAACAUCUGCUCUGUUUACCCCUGACAAAACUGCUACUCGUGGGGCAAUGCAAGUCUUUCCCACAUUUGUUUUAUUUUAUGGCUAAAAGUCAUUUCUGCAUUUGCAAAUUACUUCCAAAGCCUACCUUCCUUGAGCUCUUUAACUCUCUAUAGUCUUCUGGUAAUUUUCUUUAGAUUUCCCUUUUCAGAACCCUUUUGUGACACUGAAAACCUGAGUUUUCAAACUGAUACAUCUACCUGAGAAUUUUCACAUAUAAUUUGGUCAAAAAGUUAAAAAAUAAGAAGACUUUGCCCUGUGACUGAGGUGCUCAGAAGGUAUGGCUGGCUGCUCACAAAGGCACAUAGUGAGUGAUAGGGGCUGAAAGGGCUCAGAGAAUGCCCGAGUUCUCUUAGUACAGUUUGUACAUUUUAAACCACUGUGAACUGAAAAAAAAAAAAAAGGCAACCUUGGUAGUUUAGAAAUAGAUAAGGACCCACUUAUAGAUUAAAUAAUAAUUAGCUUGUUCCAGAGAGACCAGUGAAGAUUAGUUGGUUUAUUUAAUGUGUUAGAAAGAUGGUCCUCAAAGUCCUUGAAAUGUGAAGGCGGCUUUUAUCUCCUUAAGAAAACAAGAAAACUCCACAAAAUCUUGAAAGCUAGAUAAUCCUAGCUUAAAUGAUAAAAUUUGAGUAGAGUUUGAAAACACUAAAAUCAGUUUGCCAAAUAACCAGCUCUAAUUUCUUUAUACCAAAGCCAAACUUCACCUAAAUCUUACCUAAGAAUUGAGUUCCUUAUUGUAACCAGAUAGGAGACACUUUUGUAUAUUAUUCCAAAUAUUGCAAACCUACAAGGAGUAAAAGGUGUUAUUAUUUUAAAGAAGAAGGAAUGAGGCCUGAGAGGUAUUGAUUCACUUGGUUGAGGGCUUCAAGUAGCACAAGGCAAAAGCAGGAUUUGUUGACUUCCAAACCUGUUUUCUUCCUUCACCAUGUGGCCUUUGCAUCUUUCCCACACAAAUAUUAUUCCACAAAUAUUUAUUGUCACCAACUAUAAUAAAAGAACAGAACUAUGUAUCA